GAGGCUCGGCGGAUCCCCUGCGCAGCGAGGCGAGGAGCGGACCCCAGCGCCGGUGCGUGCCGGCCCCGGGCAGCGGGACGCGGCGGGGCGGCGGCUGCAGGCAGCCGAGGAGCCGCAGGCCGAACCCAAGGCACCGGGAUUGCGCCUCCCGCGGCUGCCGGCGAACCGCGGCUCUGCAGCUCGGGGCAGGCGCGGCGGCGGCACCGGUGGUGGCCGCGGUGGCGGCAGCUGCGCGGGGACCCGCCGGGCGGCGCCUGGGUCUGGACGCGCGAGGAAGCCGCGGGAGCCUCGGCCAAGCCGCGAGCAGGUGUGAAUGAGCCCAGGGAAGGACACACGGCCACUGCUGGAGGGAUCCUCCAUUCCUGUGUCAUUUGCAUGGGUCCUGCUGUGAAAUGAACCUGGCAGGGACUUGUUAGACACUUCCUUCCUUCCCUCAUUGAGCACUCCAGUGCCAUUGUUCCACAGUUGUUCUAAUUGGGUCCUAGCUUCCUCCUGCCAAGGCAAACAGCAUAGUCUCGAGUAGGUGUCCCUAGGCUCAUCUGCCAGCCUGAACAUGAACACAGGCAAAGCUGAUGAUGGCCAGGGACCCCAGGGGACGUGGGGCCCUGUGGGGUCUGGCCCCCAGGAGCAAGACCUCUGAUGAUGCUGGUGUCUGGGAGUGAGCACCAUGCCCAUCACCCAGGACAAUGCCGUGCUGCACCUGCCCCUCCUCUACCAGUGGCUGCAGAACAGCCUGCAGGAAGGUGGGGAUGGGCCGGAGCAGCGGCUCUGCCAGGCGGCCAUCCAGAAGCUGCAGGAGUACAUCCAGCUGAACUUUGCUGUGGAUGAGAGUACGGUCCCACCUGAUCACAGCCCCCCCGAAAUGGAGAUCUGUACUGUGUACCUCACCAAGGAGCUGGGGGACACAGAGACUGUGGGCCUGAGUUUUGGGAACAUCCCUGUUUUCGGGGACUAUGGUGAAAAGCGCAGGGGGGGCAAGAAGAGGAAAACCCACCAGGGUCCUGUGCUGGAUGUGGGCUGCAUCUGGGUGACAGAGCUGAGGAAGAACAGCCCAGCAGGGAAGAGUGGGAAGGUCCGACUGCGGGAUGAGAUCCUCUCACUGAAUGGGCAGCUGAUGGUUGGAGUUGAUGUCAGUGGGGCCAGUUACCUGGCUGAGCAGUGCUGGAAUGGCGGCUUUAUCUACCUGAUCAUGCUGCGUCGCUUUAAGCACAAAGCCCACUCCACUUAUAAUGGCAACAGUAGCAACAGCUCUGAACCAGGAGAAACACCUACCUUGGAGCUGGGUGACCGAACUGCGAAAAAGGGGAAACGAACCAGAAAGUUUGGGGUCAUCUCCAGGCCUCCUGCCAACAAGGCCCCUGAAGAAUCCAAGGGCAGCGCUGGCUGUGAGGUGUCCAGUGACCCCAGCACUGAGCUGGAGAACGGCCCUGACCCUGAACUUGGAAACGGCCAUGUCUUUCAGCUAGAAAAUGGCCCAGAUUCUCUCAAGGAGGUGGCUGGACCCCAUCUAGAGAGGUCAGAAGUGGACAGAGGGACAGAGCAUAGAAUUCCAAAGACAGAUGCUCCUCUGACCACAAGCAAUGACAAACGCCGCUUCUCAAAAGGUGGGAAGACGGACUUCCAAUCGAGUGACUGCCUGGCACGGGAGGAAGUUGGCCGAAUAUGGAAGAUGGAGCUGCUCAAAGAAUCGGAUGGGCUGGGAAUUCAGGUUAGUGGAGGCCGAGGAUCAAAGCGCUCACCUCACGCUAUCGUUGUCACUCAAGUGAAGGAAGGAGGUGCCGCUCACAGGGAUGGCAGGCUGUCCUUAGGAGAUGAGCUGCUGGUAAUCAAUGGUCAUUUACUGGUCGGGCUCUCCCACGAGGAAGCAGUGGCCAUUCUUCGCUCCGCCACGGGAAUGGUGCAGCUUGUGGUGGCCAGCAAGGAAAACUCCGCAGAGGACCUCCUCAGGUUAACAUCUAAGAGCUUGCCAGAUCUGACCAGCUCGGUAGAAGAUGUGUCCUCCUGGACUGAUAACGAAGACCAGGAGGCAGACGGGGAAGAGGACGAAGGAACCAGCUCUUCUGUCCAGAGAGCAAUGCCUGGGACAGAUGAACCCCAAGAUGUGUGCGGUGCUGAGGAAUCCAAGGGGAACUUGGAAAGUCCCAAACAGGGCAGCAAUAAAAUCAAGCUCAAGAGUCGCCUUUCAGGGGGUGUACACCGCCUUGAGUCAGUUGAAGAAUAUAACGAGCUGAUGGUGCGGAAUGGGGACCCCCGGAUCCGGAUGUUGGAGGUCUCCCGAGAUGGCCGGAAACACUCCCUCCCGCAGCUGCUGGACUCUUCCAGUGCCUCACAGGAAUACCACAUUGUGAAGAAGUCUACCCGCUCCUUAAGCACGACUCAGGUGGAAUCUCCUUGGAGGCUCAUUCGGCCAUCCGUCAUCUCGAUCAUUGGGUUGUACAAAGAAAAAGGCAAGGGCCUUGGCUUUAGUAUUGCUGGAGGUCGAGACUGCAUUCGUGGACAGAUGGGGAUUUUUGUCAAGACCAUCUUCCCAAAUGGAUCAGCUGCAGAGGACGGAAGACUUAAAGAAGGGGAUGAAAUCCUAGAUGUAAAUGGAAUACCAAUAAAGGGCUUGACAUUUCAAGAAGCCAUUCAUACCUUUAAGCAAAUCCGGAGUGGAUUAUUUGUUUUAACGGUACGCACAAAGUUGGUGAGCCCCAGCCUCACACCCUGCUCGACACCCACACACAUGAGCAGAUCCGCCUCCCCGAACUUCAAUACCAGUGGGGGAGCCUCAGCGGGAGGUUCCGAUGAAGGCAGUUCUUCAUCCCUGGGUCGGAAGACCCCUGGGCCCAAGGACAGGAUCGUCAUGGAAGUAACACUCAACAAAGAGCCAAGAGUUGGAUUAGGCAUUGGUGCCUGCUGCUUGGCUCUGGAAAACAGUCCUCCUGGCAUCUACAUUCACAGCCUUGCUCCAGGAUCAGUGGCCAAGAUGGAGAGCAACCUGAGCCGCGGGGAUCAAAUCCUGGAAGUGAACUCCGUCAACGUCCGCCAUGCUGCUUUAAGCAAAGUCCACGCCAUCUUGAGUAAAUGCCCUCCAGGACCCGUUCGCCUUGUCAUCGGCCGGCACCCUAAUCCAAAGGUUUCCGAGCAGGAAAUGGAUGAAGUCAUAGCACGCAGCACUUAUCAGGAGAGCAAAGAGGCCAAUUCCUCUCCUGGCUUAGGUACCCCCUUGAAGAGUCCCUCUCUUGCAAAAAAGGACUCCCUUAUUUCUGAAUCUGAACUCUCCCAGUACUUUGCCCACGAUGUCCCUGGCCCCUUGUCAGACUUCAUGGUGGCCGGUUCUGAGGACGAGGAUCACCCGGGAAGUGGCUGCAGCACGUCGGAGGAGGGCAGCCUGCCUCCCAGCACCUCCACUCACAAGGAGCCUGGAAAACCCAGAGCCAACAGCCUCGUGACUCUUGGGAGCCAUCGGGCUUCUGGGCUCUUCCACAAGCAGGUGACAGUUGCCAGACAAGCCAGUCUCCCCGGAAGCCCACAGGCCCUCCGAAACCCUCUCCUCCGCCAGAGGAAGGUAGGCUGCUACGAUGCCAACGAUGCCAGUGAUGAGGAAGAGUUUGACAGAGAAGGGGACUGCAUUUCACUCCCAGGGGCCCUCCCGGGUCCCAUCAGGCCUCUGUCAGAGGAUGACCCGAGGCGUGUCUCAAUUUCCUCUUCCAAGGGCAUGGACGUCCACAACCAAGAGGAACGACCCCGGAAAACACUGGUGAGCAAGGCCAUCUCGGCACCUCUUCUUGGUAGCUCAGUGGACUUAGAGGAGAGUAUCCCAGAGGGCAUGGUGGAUGCUGCGUCCUAUGCAGCCAACCUCACGGACUCUGCAGAGGCCCCCAAGGGGAGCCCUGGAAGCUGGUGGAAGAAGGAACUGUCAGGAUCAAGUAGCGCACCCAAAUUGGAAUACACAGUCCGUACAGACACCCAGAGUCCGACGAACACUGGGAGCCCCAGUUCCCCCCAGCAGAAAAGUGAAGGCCUGGGCUCCAGGCACAGACCAGUGGCCAGGGUAAGCCCCCACUGCAAGAGAUCCGAGGCUGAGGCCAAGCCCAGUGGCUCACAGACAGUGAACCUGACUGGCAGAGCCAAUGAUCCAUGCGAUCUGGACUCGAGAGUCCAGGCCACUUCUGUCAAAGUGACUGUCGCUGGCUUUCAGCCAGGUGGAGCUGUGGAGAAGGAAUCUCUGGGAAAGCUGACCACUGGAGAUGCUUGUGUCUCUACCAGCUGUGAACUAGCCAGUGCUCUGUCCCAUCUGGAUGCCAGCCACCUCACAGAGAACCUGCCCAAAGCUGCAUCAGAGCUGGGGCAACAACCCAUGACUGAACUGGACAGCUCCUCAGACCUCAUCUCUUCCCCAGGGAAGAAGGGGGCCGCUCAUCCUGACCCCAGCAAGACCUCUGUAGACACAGGGCAAGUCAGUCGGCCAGAGAAUCCCAGCCAGCCUGCAUCGCCCAGGGUCACCAAGUGCAAGGCCAGGUCUCCAGUCAGGCUCCCCCAUGAGGGCAGCCCCUCCCCGGGGGAGAAAGCAGCGGCUCCCCCUGACUACAGCAAGACUCGAUCAGCAUCGGAAACCAGCACACCCCACAAUACCAGGAGGGUGGCUGCCCUCAGGGGAGCGGGACCUGGAGCAGAGGGAAUGACACCAGCUGGUGCUGUCCUGCCAGGAGACCCCCUCACAUCCCAGGAGCAGAGACAGGGAGCUCCAGGUAACCACAGUAAGGCUCUGGAAAUGACAGGAAUCCAUGCACCUGAAAGCUCCCAGGAGCCUUCCCUGCUGGAGGGAGCAGAUUCUGUGUCCUCAAGGGCACCGCAGGCCAGCCUCUCCAUGCUGCCAUCCACUGACAACACCAAAGAAGCAUGUGGCCAUGUCUCGGGGCACUGCUGCCCAGGGGGGAGUAGAGAGAGCCCUGUGACGGACAUUGACAGCUUCAUCAAGGAGCUGGAUGCUUCUGCAGCAAGGUCUCCGUCUUCCCAGACGGGGGACAGUGGCUCUCAGGAGGGCAGUGCUCAGGGCCACCCACCAGCCGGGGCUGGAGGUGGGAGCUCCUGCCGUGCCGAACCAGUCCCGGGGGGCCAGACCUCCUCCCCGAGGAGGGCCUGGGCUGCUGGUGCCCCCGCCUACCCACAAUGGGCCUCCCAGCCUUCGGUUUUAGAUUCAAUUAAUCCCGACAAACAUUUUACUGUGAACAAAAACUUUCUGAGCAACUACUCUAGAAAUUUUAGCAGUUUUCAUGAAGACAGCACCUCCCUAUCAGGCCUGGGUGACAGCACGGAGCCGUCUCUGUCAUCCAUGUAUGGCGAUGCUGAGGAUUCUUCUUCUGACCCUGAGUCACUCACUGAAGCCCCACGAGCUUCUGCCAGGGACGGCUGGUCCCCUCCUCGUUCCCGUGUGUCUUUGCACAAGGAAGAUCCUUCGGAGUCAGAAGAGGAACAGAUUGAGAUUUGUUCCACACGUGGCUGCCCCAAUCCACCCUCGAGUCCUGCUCAUCUUCCCACCCAGGCUGCCAUCUGUCCUGCCUCAGCCAAAGUUCUGUCAUUAAAAUACAGCACUCCGAGAGAGUCGGUGGCCAGUCCCCGUGAGAAGGCCGCCUGCUUGCCAGGCUCAUACACUUCAGGCCCAGACUCUUCCCAGCCAUCAUCACUCUUGGAGAUGAGCUCUCAGGAGCAUGAAACUCAUGCGGACAUAAGCACUUCACAGAACCACAGGCCCUCGUGUGCAGAAGAAACCACAGAAGUCACCAGCGCUAGCUCAGCCAUGGAAAACAGUCCGCUGUCUAAAGUAGCCAGGCAUUUUCACAGUCCGCCCAUCAUUCUCAGCUCCCCCAACAUGGUAAAUGGCUUGGAACAUGACCUGCUAGAUGACGAAACCCUGAAUCAAUACGAAACAAGCAUUAAUGCAGCUGCCAGUCUGUCCUCCUUCAGUGUGGAUGUCCCUAAGAAUGGAGAAUCUGUUUUGGAAAACCUCCACAUCUCUGAAAGUCAAGACCUGGAUGACUUGCUACAGAAACCAAAAAUGAUCGCUAGGAGGCCCAUCAUGGCCUGGUUUAAAGAAAUAAAUAAACAUAACCAAGGCACACAUUUGAGGAGCAAAACCGAGAAGGAACAACCUCUAAUGCCUGCCAGAAGUCCCGACUCCAAGAUUCAGAUGGUGAGUUCAAGCCAAAAAAAGGGCGUUACUGUGCCUCAUAGCCCUCCUCAGCCGAAAACAAACCUGGAAAAUAAGGACCUGUCUAAGAAGAGUCCGGCAGAAAUGCUUCUGACUAAUGGUCAGAAGGCAAAGUGUGGUCCGAAGCUGAAGAGGCUCAGCCUCAAGGGCAAGGCCAAAGUCAACUCUGAGGCCCCUGCUGCGAAUGCUGUGAAGGCUGGGGGGACGGACCACAGGAAACCCUUGAUCUCACCCCAGACCUCCCACAAAACACUUUCUAAGGCAGUGUCACAGCGGCUCCAUGUAGCCGACCACGAGGACCCUGACAGAAACACCACAGCUGCCCCCAGGUCCCCCCAGUGUGUGCUGGAAAGCAAGCCACCUCUUGCCACCUCUGGGCCACUGAAACCCUCAGUGUCUGACACGAGCAUCAGGACAUUUGUCUCGCCCCUGACCUCUCCCAAGCCUGUUCCUGAGCAAGGCAUGUGGAGCAGGUUCCACAUGGCUGUCCUCUCUGAACCCGACAGAGGUUGCCCAACCACCCCUAAAUCUCCUAAGUGUAGAGCAGAGGGCAGGGCGCCCCGUGCUGACUCCGGGCCGGUGAGUCCGGCAGCGUCUAGGAACGGCAUGUCCGUGGCAGGGAACAGACAGAGUGAGCCGCGCCUGGCCAGCCAUGUGGCAGCAGACACAGCCCAACCCAGGCCGACUGGCGAAAAAGGAGGCAACAUAAUGGCCAGCGAUCGCCUCGAAAGAACAAACCAGCUGAAAAUCGUGGAGAUUUCUGCUGAAGCAGUGUCAGAGACUGUAUGUGGUAACAAGCCAGCUGAAAGCGACAGACGGGGAGGGUGCUUGGCCCAGGGCAACUGUCAGGAGAAGAGUGAAAUCAGGCUCUAUCGCCAGGUCGCAGAAUCAUCCACAAGUCAUCCAUCCUCACUCCCAUCUCAUGCCUCCCAGGCAGAGCAGGAAAUGUCACGAUCAUUCAGCAUGGCAAAACUGGCGUCCUCCUCCUCCUCCCUUCAAACAGCCAUUAGAAAGGCAGAAUACUCCCAGGGAAAAUCAAGCCUGAUGUCAGACUCCCGAGGGGUGCCCAGAAACAGCAUUCCAGGGGGCCCCUCGGGGGAGGACCAUCUCUACUUCACCCCAAGGCCAGCGACCAGGACCUACUCCAUGCCAGCCCAGUUCUCAAGCCAUUUUGGACGGGAGGGUCACCCCCCACACAGCCUGGGUCGCUCUCGGGACAGCCAGGUCCCUGUGACAAGCAGUGUUGUCCCCGAGGCAAAGGCAUCCAGAGGUGGUCUUCCCAGCCUGGCUAAUGGACAGGGCAUAUAUAGUGUAAAGCCGCUGCUGGACACAUCGAGGAAUCUUCCAGCCACAGAUGAAGGGGAUAUCAUUUCAGUCCAGGAGACGAGCUGCCUAGUCACAGACAAAAUCAAAGUCACCAGACGACACUACUGCUAUGAGCAGAACUGGCCCCAUGAAUCUACCUCAUUUUUCUCUGUGAAGCAGCGGAUCAAGUCUUUUGAGAACCUGGCCAAUGCUGACCGGCCUGUAGCCAAGUCCGGGGCUUCCCCAUUUUUGUCGGUGAGCUCCAAGCCUCCCAUUGGGAGGCGGUCUUCCGGCAGCAUUGUUUCCGGGAGCCUGGGCCACCCAGGUGACGCAGCAGCAAGGUUGUUGAGACGCAGCUUGAGUUCCUGCAGCGAAAACCAAAGCGAAGCCGGCACCCUCCUGCCCCAGAUGGCCAAGUCUCCCUCAAUCAUGACACUGACCAUCUCUCGGCAGAACCCACCAGAGACCAGUAGCAAGGGCUCUGAUUCGGAACUAAAGAAAUCACUUGGUCCUUUGGGAAUUCCCACCCCAACGAUGACCCUGGCUUCUCCUGUUAAGAGGAACAAGUCCUCGGUACGCCACACGCAGCCCUCGCCCGUGUCCCGCUCCAAGCUCCAGGAGCUGAGAGCCUUGAGCAUGCCUGACCUUGACAAGCUCUGCAGCGAGGAUUACUCAGCAGGGCCGAGCGCCGUGCUCUUCAAAACUGAGCUGGAGAUCACCCCCAGGAGGUCACCUGGCCCUCCUGCUGGAGGCGUUUCGUGUCCCGAGAAGGGCGGGAACAGGGCCUGUCCAGGAGGAAGUGGCCCUAAAACCAGUGCUGCUGAGACACCCAGUUCAGCCAGUGAUACGGGUGAAGCUGCCCAGGAUCUGCCUUUUAGAAGAAGCUGGUCAGUUAAUUUGGAUCAACUUCUAGUCUCAGCGGGGGACCAGCAAAGAUUACAGUCUGUUUUAUCGUCAGUGGGAUCGAAAUCUACCAUCCUAACUCUCAUUCAGGAAGCGAAAGCACAAUCAGAGAAUGAAGAAGAUGUUUGCUUCAUAGUCUUGAAUAGAAAAGAAGGCUCAGGUCUGGGAUUCAGUGUGGCAGGAGGGACAGAUGUGGAGCCAAAAUCAAUCACGGUCCACAGGGUGUUUUCUCAGGGGGCGGCUUCUCAGGAAGGGACUAUGAACCGAGGGGAUUUCCUUCUGUCAGUCAACGGCGCCUCACUGGCUGGCUUAGCCCACGGGAAUGUCCUGAAGGUUCUGCACCAGGCACAGCUGCACAAAGAUGCCCUCGUGGUCAUCAAGAAAGGGAUGGAUCAGCCCAGGCCCUCUGCCCGGCAGGAGCCUCCCACAGCCAAUGGGAAGGGUUUGCUGUCCAGAAAGACCAUCCCCCUGGAGCCUGGCAUUGAAAACACAGAACAAAGGAUGCAAGUACAGCAGCAACACAGCCAGGAGGGCAGCCCCAGAAUUGGGAGGCCAACAGUGCUACUGGGCUCAAGUGCUGUUAUAAGGAGAAGUGUGGCUGUACACGAUGCUCUGUGUGUUGAAGUGCUGAAGACCUCGGCUGGGCUGGGACUGAGUCUGGAUGGGGGAAAAUCAUCGGUGACGGGAGAUGGGCCCUUGGUCAUUAAAAGAGUGUACAAAGGUGGUGCGGCUGAACAAGCUGGAAUAAUAGAAGCUGGAGAUGAAAUUCUUGCUAUUAAUGGGAAACCUCUGGUUGGGCUCAUGCACUUUGAUGCCUGGAAUAUUAUGAAGUCUGUCCCAGAAGGACCUGUGCAGUUAUUAAUUAGAAAGCAUAGGAAUUCUUCAUGAAUUUUAACAAGAAUCAUUUUCUCAGUUCUCUUCUUUCUUUAGCAAAUCAGAGUGACUUCUUUAAACCACAGGUUGUUGAAAUGGCCAACACUGGUACAGACACGGACUAUAAAAAUCUCCAAGCUUGUGCUUACACAUGAAGCCUGACUUAACUGUAUGUGCAACAGCAAUGAAAUUAACUCCAGAAGCCUUCCACCUGCGUCACCCAGGCCGGGAGGGUUCCUUCGUUCCAGUGCCUGUCCCCUACCUUUAUGUUAUGUUUACUGAUGGGGAUACAAGAUGUGACACACCCUUCUUUAUUUGAAACAAACAAACAUUUAGCUAGACCUUUGCUUCCUUCUUGCCAGCUCUCCCAACAUACCCAAUCCUGGUGAUCAGGGAACUAAAAGUCUGAGGGGGACACAAAUGUCACACCUAAGAGGACAAUCAAUCAUUUUGUAUGAUUUUGUAAGUAAAUGACAGAAUGCUUUUAGGCACAUUCAAUGGAAGGAGGAGAUGUAGGUCUGUAUAUGUUACCCUGAAAAGAGAAUAAGACUUACUUAAAAAAAUGAAUUAUGACCUGUUAGGCUGAGCUCAGGAAUUGUCCAAAAAGGAAAAAGCAAAAUAAUUAAUUGAGAGUAUUUUUUAGUGAGUGUAAUGUAUAAUGUACGUAUGCAAAGUUCAACUCAAUAGGUUAUUGAUCACCAUGAAGUAUUGAUCAUUUUCUAUCUCAAAAGUGUAAGCCAUAAGGCUGUUUUACAGAAUAGCACUUCUGAUAAGCUGUAUUAAAUAGCCAUGAGCUUCACUGCUUAGAGGGAGCAGAAAGGUCAACAUCUAAAAGCACCUUACAACUAGUUUUUGAACCUGUCUUGAUAAGUGCUUGAAUUCAAGACUGGUCAGUCCAAGAGCAGACAAAAAUAUCACAAGUCAGUCAGUCACUGGGUUUCCAUUUCUGAAUUUUAUGCACUCCAACCAUGAAUUUAAACUAAAUUUUUAGAAAUCAAGUAUCUUUCUAAGUGUCCUUGGAUUUAUAGACAAUGUAUGUACAAUCCAAAUAGAGGAGCUUAAUGGAAUCCUUUUAGGAGACUGGUUGGUUUUUUUCCCUCUUUCCCAACAUGUUUAAGAAAUGUAACAUUCUAAGUAUUGGAUCUCUUUUCUUGACCUAGUAUAAUGACAACUGCAGUGACUUAAGUUUUUGCUGUUUUCGUUUUCCCGCUUUGCAAUUUCCUCCUUUUGCCAAAAAUGUUUUCCUACAGAAGACUGUCGUGACUCACGCUACUUGGGAAACUCACUCUGGCCACUCCUCCUCUGGUGGCAUGAGCUGCUUCCCAGUAGCUAUUCCGAUUGGAUAUUCCGUUCGUCGUCACAUAGCUGGCUUUUCUCUCCUCAUGAUGUACCUUAUUUUCUUAGGUAAAUAAUUCCAAACUCUCAUCGGGUCAUAAAGAGGAGGAGAAACAGGGUGAGUCAAGGUAAAGGAGCAGAAAUGUAGUUACAAGCCAGGUCGUCUUCAGUGGCACAAACCAACCCGUUGAGCCCUGACAACAUGAGUGGAGAGUGCAUUUGCCAUACCUGUGUGCAUGACACUAAGAUUUUAUGUUGGAGAUACUUCUUUAAAUAACCUACAGCUUGGGUCUAUGGCUGUGACCCCCAGAUUCAUGGAGGGGCUUUAGCCAUCAGCUUUGUACAUCAUCAUUUUUCUGAAUGACCAAUCCCACUAAACAUCUUUGAAGUCGGCCUAGAGAGGUCCUUCAGAUGAGAGAGAAAUAGCUGGCUUGUCUGAGUCCAGAUUUCUCAUCAACUGGCAAUACAAAGGAAAAUAUGGUACAGGAGUUAGUUAGAAAGGUCUUAUUGAUUUUACUUCUACUUUUCACUACAGUUACAGGUAGAAUACUGUAGGAAGUCAGUGCAAGGUGCAUGCUUGAUUGAUAGAUAUUGAUUGAUUGUUUUUCAGUCUCUGGGGUCAGUUUUGUGGUUUCUGCUUUCUUGCCUAAAUCAAAGACUAUUUCAAGUCAACAACACUGAAAACUGCUUUUCGCCUCCACUCUUACAGCUGUGCCUAAUAAUAAUUAAUUAAUAAACGCACAGCCCUAUGUGAACAGACAGGAAUUUCUUGUGCAAUGUGGAGCAAAUGGAAUGGUCUCCUUCCGCAAGUCUUUUUAAUCCUCAUAUCUGGAGUACAAGGGUAGACCUCUGGCUUACCACAUACACUAUGCUAAAGUCAUCAGCCACUGCUACUACAUCUUGCCAGAAGGUUUCCCUCGCCAACAAACAGUUGAAAUUUAAGGGAAGAAGCAAAAGCUAAACUGUCUUUGACCCUAAGAUAGAUAGAAAGCUAUUUAUUUGUCUUCAGUGUUCAAGGCAUGACUAGUAUUUCUAAUUAGCCUAAUAAAUUCCCACACUUUCUGAAGUGAACACUAAUGGUAUUGUCCUACUAAAACUGUCAUUGUUUCUUUUUUUUUAACUGGUCAGUCAUUCACAAUAAGCUAUGAGGGUAAAUAAAUAUGUGUUAUAACAAGUAAACCGUAGUUGCAAGAAUAUACCAUGAAGAUUAAAGUAGGCUGGGUUUCAUUUCCAUCUUCCCACACAUCUCAUUGAAUUUGAUGGUUGACUUAAUUGGCACCAUAACUUUGUAUGAUAUUAUACAUUAACCUUUAUUUAUGUAAAGUAAAAUGCCUUAUAUAUUAAAGAGUAAGUGCAAUAAUAUGAAAUAGCCUGUACAUUUUAAAAAUGUUGUCACCAAGUUAUAUAAAUCCACAUCUCUGUAAACAACCUUUUUUAAGUAAUUUUAAAAAAAAUAAACACUCUGCUUACUACUUGA